GCUCCCCCUCGGCAGCUGUUGUGGGGCACCAUGCGAGGCUUCGGGCCAGGCUUGACGGCCAGGCGUCUCCUCCCGCUGCGGUUGCCCCCGCGGCCGCCCGGGCCCCGGCUGGCGAGCGGGCAGGCGGCCGGCGCCCUGGAGCGGGCCAUGGACGAGCUGCUGCGCCGCGCGGUGCCGCCGACGCCGGCCUACGAGCUGCGCGAGAAGACACCGGCGCCCGCCGAGGGUCAGUGCGCGGACUUCGUGAGCUUCUACGGUGGGCUGGCCGAGACGGCCCAGCGGGCCGAACUGCUGGGCCGCCUGGCGCGGGGCUUCGGCGUGGACCACGGCCAGGUGGCGGAGCAGAGCGCCGGCGUGCUCCAUCUGCGCCAGCAGCAGCGGGAGGCGGCGGUGCUGCUGCAGGCCGAGGACCGGCUGCGCUACGCGCUGGUGCCGCGCUAUCGCGGCCUCUUCCACCACAUCAGCAAGCUGGACGGCGGCGUGCGCUUCCUGGUGCAGCUGCGGGCCGACCUGCUGGAGGCGCAGGCCCUCAAGCUGGUGGAGGGGCCGGACGUCCGGGAAAUGAAUGGGGUGCUGAAAGGAAUGCUCUCAGAAUGGUUUUCCUCCGGGUUCCUGAACCUAGAACGGGUUACCUGGCAUUCACCGUGUGAAGUGCUUCAGAAAAUCAGUGAGGCUGAGGCUGUGCAUCCUGUAAAAAACUGGAUGGACAUGAAGCGCCGCGUUGGGCCCUACAGAAGGUGUUACUUCUUUUCUCACUGUUCGACCCCUGGGGAGCCCCUGGUCGUUUUGCACGUGGCACUGACUGGUGACAUCUCCAGCAACAUCCAGGCAAUCGUGAAGGAACAUCCUCCAUCAGAAACAGAAGAGAAGAACAAAAUCACUGCUGCGAUCUUUUAUUCCAUCAGCUUGACCCAGCAGGGACUCCAAGGGGUGGAGCUGGGAACAUUCCUCAUAAAGCGAGUCGUCAAGGAGUUGCAGAGAGAGUUUCCUCACCUUGGGGUGUUUUCAAGUCUGUCACCUAUACCUGGUUUCACCAAAUGGCUUCUGGGGCUUCUGAACUCGCAAACGAAGGAGCAUGGGAGGAAUGAACUCUUUACAGAUUCGGAAUGUAAGGAAAUCUCGGAGAUCACAGGUGGCCCCAUUAACGAGACCCUCAAGCUCCUCCUCAGCAGCAGCGAGUGGGUGCAGUCGGAGAAGCUGGUGCGGGCGCUGCAGACUCCGCUGAUGAGGCUGUGCGCCUGGUACCUGUAUGGAGAGAAGCACCGCGGCUACGCGCUGAACCCCGUGGCCAACUUCCACCUGCAGAACGGGGCGGUGCUGUGGCGCAUCAACUGGAUGGCGGAUGUGAGCCUCAGAGGCAUCACCGGCUCCUGCGGCCUGAUGGCCAACUACCGCUACUUCCUGGAGGAGACGGGCCCCAACAGCACCUCCUACCUCGGCUCCAAGAUCAUCAAAGCCUCUGAGCAGGUCCUCAGCCUAGUGGCCCAGUUUCAAAAGAACAGCAAGCUCUGACAGUAAACCUCUCCUAAAGCACAGGGCCCCGGCUAAGAAAACGAUCAUUUUCAGGAGGGGCCGGGAGUUAUGUAUCUGAAGCAGCUUUCCAAGCAAAGCCAAAGUUGACUGUGUUCUUGUCCCGCAGCCGGUCCACACUGUGAGGCCAGGCCUCAACUUCCCUCACCCUGGGCGUGACAUGCACCCAGUGCAAGACGGUUGUGGGUGCGGGUGCACACAAAUGAGUGGGUUGCUGUGCUGUCUCCGGAAGAUUCUGUCGUUGCCCUUGGCCUGGCUCCCUGCCCGGGGCUGGUGCUGUGGUACCUACAUCUUCAGGAAGCUGUGCAGCCUCUGCCAUUGCCAUCCCAGGGGGAUCUGGCAUCCUCCUAAGGACCGGGGCGCGUGGCCCAGAUAAGAAUAGGUGUUCCUUUGUGCUCAUAAAACAGAAUGCGGCGAUGGUUGCUUUAGCCGUUUCUCACCAUGCAAUGCAGAGGGACAAAGGGCUGUGCUACACUUCCCAGUUACAUUCUGAAGCUCAUAAAUGUAUGAGAAGGUUUGUGAUUUUGCACAAGGUGUGUGUAGUAAGUUAAAUUGUUGAACACAAAAAUGUUGCUGCUUGAGGCAUAAGUUGGAUAAUAGGCUUUAAAUGAUCAGGGAUUCAGGUUCAUAAUGAACUUCACAGUAAAGAACACGUUUGUUCUGUAAAGCAUUGAACAUCUGAUUGUGUAGUGGUGGUCGUCUUUAAGAUUAGAGACCUGGGAAGGCUGGAAUCAGCCAGCCAGCCUACGGGGAGUUUGGGAUGAAGGAGCCUGGGGUGUGUUGGAUGAGAACAAAGGUGAAGGAAGGGGCAGUCAUUGUGCUUGUGGGAGGAAGGCAGUUGUGUUUGUGUGUGUAUGUGUGUAUCAGUGCACAUCUGUGUGCAUGUGCACGAGCGUCUCUGUGUGGAUCAGUGCACGUCUGUGCGUGUGCACGAGCGUCUGUGGAUCAGUGCACGUCUGUGUGCGUGUGCACGAGCGUCUCUGUGUGUAUCAGUGCAUGUCUGUGUACGUGUGCACGAGCAUCUCUGGAUCAGUGCACGUCUGUGUGCAUGUGCCCGAGCGUCUCUGUGUGGAUCAGUGCACGUCUGUGUGCGUGUGCACGAGCGUCUCUGUGUGGAUCAGUGCACGUCUGUGUGCGUGUGCACGAGCAUCUCUGUGUGUGUCAGUGCACGUCUGUGUGCGUGUGCACGAGCGUCUCUGUGUGUAUCAGUGCACGUCUGUGUGCGUGUGCCCGAGCGUCUCUGUGUGGAUCAGUGCACGUCUGUGUGCAUGUGCACGAGCGUUCUAUGUGGAUCAGUGCACGCCUGUGUGCGUGUGCACGAGCGUCUCUGUGUGUCAGUGCACGUCUGUGUGCGUGUGCCCGAGCGUCUCUGUGUGGAUCAGUGCACGUCUGUGUGCGUGUGCACGAGCGUCUCUGUGUGGAUCAGUGCACGUCUGUGUGCGUGUGCACGAGCGUUCUAUGUGGAUCAGUGCACGCCUGUGUGCGUGUGCACGAGCGUCUCUGUGUGUCAGUGCACGUCUGUGUGCGUGUGCACAAGCGUCUCUGUGUGGAUCAGUGCACGUCUGUGUGCGUGUGCACGAGCGUCUCUGUGGAUCAGUGCACGUCUGUGUGCGUGUGCACGAGCGUUCUAUGUGGAUCAGUGCACGCCUGUGUGCGUGUGCACGAGCGUCUCUGUGUGUGUCAGUGCACGUCUGUGUGUGCACGAGCGUCUCUGUGUGGAUCAGUGCACGUCUGUGUGCGUGUGCCCGAGCGUCUCUGUGUGGAUCAGUGCACGUCUGUGUGCGUGUGCACAAGCAUCUGUGUGUGUCAGUGCACGUCUGUGUGCGUGUGCACGAGCGUCUCUGGAUCAGUGCACGUCUGUGCAUGUGCACACGUGCAUGUGCAUGUGCUUACACGUCUUUGUGUGUCUGUGUGCGUGUGUCCGCAGUUGCCCUGUCCUCGCUGUCCUCGGUUUGGCAGACAGGUCCCUCACCUUCCUUGCCUUUCAUCUCCUGUGACCCUCGCCAGGCCCCUUCUCUGUCUUCUGCGUACGGCGUGUUGCUUCGUGACAGACGGUGUGAUCGCGGGAGCUGUCUCAUGCCUCUUGUUCUCCGGGCUGAUUCUGAAAGAGUGGCUUGCAGGCCAAUCAAUGCAAUCCUGGCAACCUGCCCGCCCUUCUUGCGGGCAGAGUUCUUUACCGUAAGCGUCCCCAGACCCUCAGGCCUGCGGAAACCUGCUGGGCCUUACCGUCUUUGCUUAGCUUUUGGCCUAGACCUUAAAGACCAGCAGUCUUCUGUGCUUUAUCCUGCUGCCUCCAGAGUGCCAUGGACAGAUCACCCAUUCUCGAUCACUCCGGCAGCCUUUCGGAUCCGGUGGCGCCCUUCCUGGCUGUGUCCUUCACCUGUGCUGUCUGGUUCUCUCCUGUGUGGACAGGGGAUGAUAGGAAUUCCCGCUGCACAGGCCGCUGGGAGGACGGGCUCAGGUGACAUCUGCCGAGGCUUUGGCUCACCAGAGGAGUUUGUAGAUGUCAGUCAUCCCCAAGUCACUAGGAACUAGCACGCCUGAGGUAGGUCUCGGAAUAGUGUUCAAAUCCAUUUUACUAUUGCGGCCAAGGAGCCCUCCCUCCAGCAAGGCGGCUCAUCACAUCACGUUACUCUUUAGGUCAAAUGUAACCCUCCCGGUUUUAUUUAUCACUCAGGCAGAGUUUCUUAACCUUUUGUGAGUUACAGAUCACUGAAAUUCUGGUGAAAGCCAGGUAGGCCUCGCCGCAGGAGAACACAUACAUGGUGCACAGAACACACACAGUGCACAGAACACAGUGCACAGGAGAACACUCACAGUGCACAGGAGAACACGCACACGGUGCACAGGAGAACACGCACACAUGUUGCACAGGAGAAUUCACACACAGUGCACAGGAGAACACACAGUGCACAGGAGAACACAUGGUGCACAGGAGAACACGCACACACGGUGCACAGGAGAACACACACAGUGCACAGGAGAACACGCACAGUGCACAGGAGAACACAGAGUGCACAGGAGAACACAUGGUGCACAGGAGAACACGCACACACGGUGCACAGAACACACACAGUGCACAGGAGAACACGCACAGUGCACAGGAGAACACGGUGCACCGGAGAACAUGCACACAUGGUGCACAGGAGAACACAGUGCACAGGAGAAUACAGACUGCACAGAACACACGCACAGUGCACAGGAGAAAACGCACACACAGUGCACAGAACACAGUGCACAGGAGAACACGCACACAGUGCACAGAGAACCACACAGUGCACAGGAGAAUACGCACACACAGUGCACAGAACACAGACACAGUACACAGGAGAACACGCACACACAGUGCACAGAACACAGCCAGUGCACAGGAGAACACUGCACAGGAGAACCACACUGCACAGGAGAAUAUGCAUAAACAGUUCACAGGAGAACACGCACACACAGUGCAUAGAGCACAGACACAGUGCACAGGAGAACCACACAAUGUACAGGAGAAUACGCACACACAGUGCACAGGAGAACAUACACGCAGUACACAGACACAGUGCACCGGAGAACACAGUGCACAGGAGAACACGCACACACAGUGCACAGAACACAGACACAGUGCACAGGAGAACACACAGUGCACAGGAGAACACAGUGCACAGGAGAAUACACACGGUGCACAGGAGAAUUCACACACAAUGCACAGGAGAACACAGUGCACAGGAGAACACACACACACACUGCACAGGAGACCAUGCACAGUGCACAGGAGAAUACACAUGGUGCACAGCAGAAUUCACACAGUGCACAGGAGAACACACACAGUGCACAGAAUUCAUGCACACAGUGCACAGGAGAACACACACAGUGCACAGGAGAACACAGUGCACAGGAGAACACACACUGCACAGAACAAAUGCACAGCACACAGGAGAACAUGCACACACAGUGCACAGGAGAACACAGUGCACAGGAGAACACACAGUGCACAGGAGAGAACACACAGUGCACAGAACACACAGGGCACAGGAGAACACACAGUGCACAGGAGAACACUGCACAGAACACACGGUGAUCAGAACACACAGUGCACAGGAGAACACACAGUGCACAGAACACACGGGGCACAGGAGAACACACGAUGCACGGAACACGGUGAUCAGAACACGGUUCACAGGAGAACACACAGUGCACAGAACACACGGGGCACAGGAGAACACACAGUGCACAGAACACACAGUGCACAGAACACACGGUGCACAGGAGAACACAUGGUGCACAGGAGAACACACGGUGUACAGAACACACGGUGCACAGGAGAACACGCAGUGCACAGGAGAACAUGCAAUGCACGGGAGAACACAGUGCAGAGAACACACACGCACUGCACAGAACAUGCAGUGGUGCACAGGAGAACAGUACACAACAACACAUUCCAUGCACAGGAGAACACACGCAAUUCACAGGACACAACAGAACACACGCAGUGCACAGGACACAACAGAACACACGUGCACAGGAGAACACAGUACACACACAGCGCACUGGAGAACACGCACAGUGCACAGGAGAACAGAGUGCACAGAACACAGUCCACAGGACAGCACACGGUACACAGCAGAACACCCGCAGUGCACAGGAGAACCUAGUGCACAGAACACACACCCUGUGCACAGUUUUGUUUUGUUUUGCUUUUGCAAUUCCAGGGAGCUCCCUGGCCUCCCACAGCCAUUCAUAGAGCCCAUUCUGUUUGCGAUAAAAACAGAUCUCCUCCAGCUCACGUGAGGCUAGGCACGGGUUCCUCAAAACCUUUUUGGGCAGCUAGCAGCUUUGACUAGCAGCUCAUCUCACCAGGCUGAGGUCGCUGCCUGUGAACAGUUGACAGACCUAAAGCCAGCCAGAAUGUUCUGUGUCAGAGAGCCCUGUCCAAUGGGCAGAGCUGGGAGACACGCAGGAAGACCCCCAGCCCAUGCCCGUUCUCAGGCCUGAGGUUCAUUCUCGUUCUCUCCCUCUUCCCUUUCCCCUUCCUCCCUCCUGCCCUCGAAUCUGCAAGGUCUCUCCGGGUGGCUGUGUUCUGCCAGGGCCUCCCAGGCUCCAAGAUCACUGCCUUCAGGGAGCCCAGGAAGAGCUGCACAUCCGCUGCCUCUGUGUGGCAGGCGUGUCCGAGACUGCAACUCCUAGUUCCCACCUUUCACACCUCAUCUCUCUAACCUCUUAUGGAAAAUUUCAAACAUAUGUAAAAGCAGGGAGAAAUUGCAUAACGAACCUACAGACCUAUCACCCAGCUUCCACAGUCAUCAGUGGUUUUCUGUUUUUAUCAAACUUUAUCUUUGUACUUCUUACAGUGCUUCACAUUUAGCAGGUCCUCAAUGAACAUUAGAUGGAUGGAUGGAAGGAAGGAAGAUGGAUGGAUGGAUGGAUGGAUGGAUGGAUGGAUGGAUGGAUGACAGAUGGAUGGUGGAGGGUUAAUGGAAGGAAGGAAGAUGGAUGGGUGGAAGGAAGAUGGGUGGAUGGAUGGUGGAGGGUGGAUAGAAGGAAGAUGGGUAUAUGAAUAGAUGGCUGGGUGGGUGGAAGGAAGGAAGAUGGUUGGAUGGAUGGAAGAUGGAUGGAUGGAUGGAUGGAGGGUAGAGUUUUAAUGGAAGGAAGAUGGAUGGACGAAUAGAUGGAAGGAAGAUGGGUGGAUGGAAGGAAGAUGGAUGGAUGGAAUGAUGGAUGGGUGGUAGAGGGUGGAUGGAAGGAAGAUGGAUGAAUAGAUGGGUGGGUGGGUGGAUGUUUGGAUGGAUGGUGGAGGGCAGAGUGUUAAUGGAAGGAAGAUGAAUGGAUAGAUGGAGGGUAGAGUGUAGAUGGAAGGAAAGGAAAGGAGGAUGGAUGGAUGGAUGGAUGGAUAGAUGGAUGGAGGAGGGUGGAUGGAAGGAAGGAGGAUGGAUGGAUGGAUGGGUGGGUGGGUGGGUGGAUGGAUGGCGCAGGGUAUAUGGAAGGAAGAUGGAUGAAUGAUGGAAGAUGGAUGGAUGGGGGACAGAUGAAUUGAUGGCGGAGGAUGUUAGGAUGGGUGGAUGGAUGUAUUAACAUCCCUUCUCCAUGCCUCAGUCCCCAUCAUAAGGAGAAAGAGCCUGUCGUCCCUCUAUGAUACUGCACUGAACCAAUAUUCCCCUCACUUCAUGGGUGUUACAAACCUCUUAUCAUCUGUUUACGUCUCACUCUUACUGUAGAACCUCUAGAAAGGCAGGUGGCUUCCAGCUCCUCGCUUUUCCUGAGGGAUGAUCUGACCACCCAUUCUUACACAUGUCAUCUUUCCCACAGUGGCAGUGCAGAGGAGACAAAAGCAGAACAAAAGCAGACAGCGGCCAGGUCUGAGGGUGAUAGGCUACUCACUGGGUCCUAGUGUUCUGAACUACACCCUACAGGAAAGUGCUACUCAGUGCCCAGGUGACAUCGUCACAAGGGGAACACAGUGGCUAAGAGGGCAGGGGCUCAGUCUCACAGACCUGGUUUCCAUCCCACUUGCUCUCAGGAACCCUGGGCAACAACUGUGACCACAGUGUCUUCCUCUGGAAAGUGCCCAGCAGUGUUGGGCUCACCGUAGCUGCACAAUAAAUUGUCAUGAGUGCUUUCCACUGUGUCCCAGGUUCAAGGCUGAAGUCACAACCCCACCCCUGCCACAGAGCCUGCCCCCCCGAGUGUUCCCCAUCUCAGUCUGAGGCCCGACCUGUGCUUCCGGAGCCCGCGUCCCGUCCCAUCUCAGGAGCUACUCUGCUCCAUUCCCCCCGUAUCCGAGACCUAAGUUCCGGCUCUCCUUAUCUCUUGGAGCCCUGUCAUCUGUGGAUCAGAUGCUCCCCAGCUCCCUCCAUCCCACCCACAGGGUUUCACAAGAGGCCCAGCCAUGCACCCUGCUGGGGUUCAGACUUGAGGGGUGCCACUGGAGUUGGGGUGCACCUGCUCUCACCUGUUCAUGGGCUCCUUUUUCUUCUGAAAUGCAGCGUGAGGCACCAUGGAGGGAGCUGUAGACUUUGGCUCCGGCCAGUGCCCAGUUCAAAUGCUGGCCCCACCACUUCCAGCUGGGUGGCCCAGGGCAAGCCACCUACCCUUGCUUUGCCUCAGUUUCCUCAUCUUUAAGUGGCAGUAACCAUAGUACCGACCCCACAGCCUGCUGAGAGGCUCAAAGGAGACGAUGUAUAUAAAGCAGUUAACUGAUGCCUGCCCUGGGAAGCAGAGCAGUCCCUGUCAUGAUGGGCGUUUCUACAUCUGGACCUGGGCGCCACCAUCCUGCUCACCUGAAUGCGGGUUCUGGGAUCUUUCAGUCCUUAUUUGGAUAUUUGAAUAUUUGUUGGUUUUCUGGCUUCUCACAAUUUCUAAGAGGUGACUAAGUGGAUCAUUCGUUCCCGGGAGAGGUGGGAAUGGCUCCUGUGGACACGGCAUUGCACAGGGGCUUGAGGGGACCUCCUGACCCCUGAUGGCUGAGCACCCUUGUCAUACUCCUCAGGGAGAGCCCAGGCCACCGGCUAGCUCCAGACUGGCUCUGCAGGGCCUCAGAAUCUGAACUCCCUGUGGUCACUCUGAGGCCUCUCUGUCUCUCUGUGUCUUUCUCUUUCUACCCUCUCCAUCCCUCCUUCCCUCUGAGGGCUUGACCUUCACUGACCUCCAGGGCAAGAACAACCAAGAGUUGCUCCCAAGAGGGCUUCCCUCCUCCUCGUUCUGUGUGGCCUCAGAAGUGAGGGAAUCUCAGUGCUCUGUGCAGGCAUGUGCUUAUUCUGAGCUCUGUUUGAAAUUAAACAUGAGGUGUACUAAAGAUUUAAAUCGAGCAAACACCUCUGUGAUUUCCAAUUGGAUUCUGAGGCGCUUACAGAAAUAUGAAGUCCAUUUUGAUCUACUCUUAGAAACAAAAGCUGCCCAUGAUUUCACCACAGAAAGUCUGCCUCAUUUGCAGUUUAGCGGACUCACAGAGGUGACCCUAGAUCUCUGUCUCGCCUUUGUUUGGUUUAUUUCCACAUUGCAUUUGCGUUUCCCGCCUGGCUAGUUCUUGAUCAUUGAGGAAGGCAGAGAGAAACGAGAUUCUCUGCUCUGGGCCAGGCAUUCUCUGUACACGUUCCUGGUUCCAGCCUGCCUCCUUCCCUAGAGGAUCACCGUGUCCAGCCCUGAAGCUGGAGCGAGUGUUCCUCACUUAGAGAUGAGGCGAUGAGGCGGCGAGCUGGGAGAGGGCUGAGCAGCUGGUGAGGGCAGAGUUGGGACUCAAACCCAGGCCCGACCACCACCCAGCUCUCCUUCCACCGCACUGGUCCACCUCCUGACCGUACGUGGGGAGACCCACGCAAAGGCCCAGAGAGGAGAAGGCCAGCAGUGGGCAGAACAGAGUGGGCCGCAGGUUUUGGCAAGCCUGGAGGGGAAUAGGUCAGAAAGGUAGCCCGGCUGGGCUGAGAGACUGAGGACAGGGGGUGUUAGGGUGCUGACAUUCUGGCAAGGGGGCGGGGGUCUGUGGAAGACAACCCCAGGCUGGGGUGGCUUCUCUCAAACCCGGGCAUGCACAGUGCUGGCCGUAUCGGUCCGAGCCCUCGGCUGCCAGGGAGAGAAGCUGAGCUCCCACCAAAGCAUAAAAUCCAGGCCAGCGAGGGGCAGCCAGACCACGGGAAGACAGGAGGAACCCGGACCUGGCUCUCGUGCAGGAAGCAGGCAGUGCACAGCUCCGCCGCCACAGAGACAGCCUCCUCUCAUGACCCCAGACUCAGCCCGGGCCGUGGUGGGAACGAUGGUUGGCCCGGUUUGGAGAUGGGGGAUCUGGCCCUGUGGUGAGUGCACCCAGAGCAGGUGUCUCUCCGGAGCAGUUGAGUAGAACAGCUGGCGUCACCUCUUCAUGUUGACGAGGGGAGAUGAGUGGCCCAGGCAGUUCCUAGAGCGGGGGAGAUGGAGUGGGCCGUAUCCCACCCAGCAGGAGCGCUUGCUUCUGAAGCUCCCGUGCGUCUGUGACAGAGGCUUGAACCCCCGGCUUGUUCUCUCACGUCUGUUGCCGUAAAUCUGUCUCCAUCGCCUGGCACAUAGGAGAGGCUUGGCAAAUAUUUUUGGUUCACUGAAGAAAGGCAGCCCUCACUCCUGCUGCUCAGACAGCACCCCCUGAACGUGAGUUACUGCCUCCUUGAGCACUUUCGCAGGAGAGAAGACCAGAGAGCUGCCUUCAAAGAUGCCAGAGCCAUGUUUAUUUAAGCGGCGCUGCUCCAGAGAGAACUGGCCAUUUGCAGUCUCCACCCCAGUGUGGCUCACGAUGCCACCUCUCCUUGCCAGCUCUCACCGAGGCCCCCGGUGACCUCCUAGGGGGUACAUCCAGCCAGGUUCCCCCUCAGCAAUGGCCAGGGGCCACCGUGGGCCACACUGCACUUCCCAAAUGCUCCCGGCACUGGCACAGAUGCACACCCUCUUGGCCAUCCCCACCUGUGCUCCGCCACUCUUAGUCAGCCAUUCCUCUCGGCUUCCGGGAGUCCCCUCCUUCUCUAAGGAUCUCACCCCCAUCCGUGUCUCUGCUGUCUCCUAACUACCGAUAGCAAGGGCACUAGUGCCCCUGUUUGCCGGGGACAGGCCCUGUCUGGGGCCCUGGUGUGGCAUCAUUGUUAACAGAGCUUCUUUUCACUCUGAAGUGUUCAGUUAGGACAGUCACUUGCACAGUCCCCUCACUGGUGACACAGACACCCCAUACCUGUGUGUUUCCCCUGCAUAGCUCAGCAGCAGCUCAGGCUCAGCACGGCCAAGGCUGAAUGCAGAUGCCCUCCCUCCAAAACCUGGCCUCCUCCAGCUGUUCCUUCCUGGCGAGGCCACCUCCAACUGUGUAACACAGAAGCCUGGGUGCCAUCCCUGGGGCUCCCCUCACCCCCACCUCCCACCCGUCCCCGGGCCCCUGGACAGACCACUGGCCUUGUUCUCUUCAUUUCCCUGGCCCAGGUUACAAAGUCUCCUUCCUGAUUAUGUGCAUUAACUAACCUCGCAGGUGCUCUGCCCACCUGCCUACGCCAGACUCUUCCAGAUCCUUCUCCACCCCAGCAGGCAGAGUUGUCAUUGUGAAAUGCAAAUCAGGUUCCAUCUCUCCUCUCCUUUCCUACCUCCCACCAUCCCCGUCACCCUCCCUGUCACACACAGCCCCCUCCGUGGCCUCUCAAGCCUGCUGUGGCCUGACCCUCCCCUCUGCUUUUCCAGGCCCUCCUGGCACUGUCCUCCCUCAGUCUGGGACUCCCUGUCCUCCCUCCUUCCUGCGUGGCACAUGCUCCUCCCUCUUCUUGAAACGCUCUCCCCUCCCUGCCUCCCAGGCAAUGCCCACUCUGCCUCCAAAGUUCAUCCAUCGUCCUCUCCUCAGGAAGAUUUCCCUGGUGGCUUGACUAGGUCACAGUCCCCCUUUAUUUGCCGUCUUCUCACUGGGGCCUCUCCUUCCUGGUAGCUUCUAAACAAGGCAGUUUCAUGUGUGUAUCUCCACUAGACUAGACGCUCUCUGAGGGCAGGGACCCUGCUUCGCUUCUGGCCCGAGGUGGCUGCAGGGUCUGCAAGAUCAUCAGGGCCCCCUCCAAUGUGACACUUGCAGAGGGGACCCCUGGCCUGGGGCCACGCUGGUUACUUGGGUACACUCCUUGCCCAGGGUUCCACAGCCCCUUAAAGGCAGGGUCUUUCUGGCCACGCCUGGCCCUGGUCUGGCCUCCCCAAGGAGCCCUGCCGCUGGGGGUGCUGUGUGGGAACAGAGCACAGGCCCUCCCUCCCAGAGCCCACGAGAUCUCACUUUCUCCAAGCCCAGCUCCCCAAGGACUCAGACCCCAGUUGCCCUGCACUGAACGCUGGCUUGCCCUAGCUCACUCGGACCCCACCCUGCACUGGGAAGGAGGGUCCCUGUCCCCGUUUGACGGGUGACGACACUGAGGCCCAGAGAGCUGAAGGGGCUGGCCGAGGGGACGGGCUUGGGCGCUUCCAUUCUCACACUGCUGCCGUGACACCUAAUCCAUCCGGGGAAGUUCCCUUUAAACCCAAAAGGGGACGGUGAAGCCACACGCGGCCGCCCUUCUCAGGAGCCCACUUCCACCUCUCGCAGGCUAGACAGCGUUCCCCAAGUCCCCCCUUGAGCUGGGUGGGCUGCCCAGCUGUGAACACAAGGACACCUCCGAUUUCGUCCUGUGAAUGUUGAUAUUAGUGGUCCCUUCCUUCAGGGGCUGUGGGGAUCUCAAAAGAUAAGGCAGGUCUGGAGUCCUGCGCGGUACCUGCCGCAUGGCAGGCUCUUUACGGACAGCGCAGGGACGCACUUUGAUGCUGAAAAUGAGUCUCUGGGACAGAUGGAUCCCAGUCUGGGUCCUCGCAAGCGCUGUGCACCCCGUCGCCGCGAGAUGGCGGUGUUGCGCCCCUCCAGCCUCCUCUGCUCUGCGCUUGGGCGCUGAAUGUUAAAAUUCCUAACAGGUGAAUCGCUUGAAUCCGGGAGGCGGAGGUUGCAGUUGGCCGAGAUGGCGCCACUCACUCCAGCCUGGCGACAGAGCGAGACUACGUCUCAAAAAAAAAUAAAAAUAAAAAAAUAAAAUCCUAA